GACGCAGGCGCACUGCACCGCGCCGCCGCCAUUUUGUGUCUGAGCCUGUGGAGCGAUUAAACCGUGCGCGGAGCUGCUUCUUUGGCGGCAGCGGCGGCGGCGGUGGCCGGUGCGGACGCGCGGAGCUCGCCGGAGACGCCGGGUGGCCGGAGCCGUGGAGCGGCGGCGGAGCGGGCGCCGCGGGGGGUGUGGCGCGGAGAAUGAUUACGGACCUGAAGCCAAAGAACAAGAUGCGCUAGUGGACAGAUUGCUGACCAGGGGCUUGAGAGCUGGGUUCUAUUUUCCCUCCUCAAACUGACUUUGCAGCCACGGAGAGGCAGGGGAAAUGGAAGGUGAUGCAGUCGAAGCCAUUGUGGAGGAGUCCGAAACUUUUAUUAAAGGAAAGGAGAGAAAGACUUACCAGAGACGCCGGGAAGGGGGCCAGGAAGAAGAUGCCUGCCACUUACCCCAGAACCAGACGGAUGGGGGUGAGGUGGUCCAGGAUGUCAACAGCAGUGUACAGAUGGUGAUGAUGGAACAGCUGGACCCCACCCUUCUUCAGAUGAAGACUGAAGUAAUGGAGGGCACAGUGGCUCCAGAAGCAGAGGCUGCUGUGGACGAUACCCAGAUUAUAACUUUACAGGUUGUAAAUAUGGAGGAACAGCCCAUAAACAUAGGAGAACUUCAGCUUGUUCAAGUACCUGUUCCUGUGACUGUACCUGUUGCUACCACUUCAGUAGAAGAACUUCAGGGGGCUUAUGAAAAUGAAGUGUCUAAAGAGGGCCUUGCGGAAAGUGAACCCAUGAUAUGCCACACCCUACCUUUGCCUGAAGGGUUUCAGGUGGUUAAAGUGGGGGCCAAUGGAGAGGUGGAGACACUAGAACAAGGGGAACUUCCACCCCAGGAAGAUCCUAGUUGGCAAAAAGACCCAGACUAUCAGCCACCAGCCAAAAAAACAAAGAAAACCAAAAAGAGCAAACUGCGUUAUACAGAGGAGGGCAAAGAUGUAGAUGUGUCUGUCUACGAUUUUGAGGAAGAACAGCAGGAGGGUCUGCUAUCAGAGGUUAAUGCAGAGAAAGUGGUUGGUAAUAUGAAGCCUCCAAAGCCAACAAAAAUUAAAAAGAAAGGUGUAAAGAAGACAUUCCAGUGUGAGCUUUGCAGUUACACGUGUCCACGGCGUUCAAAUUUGGAUCGUCACAUGAAAAGCCACACUGAUGAGAGACCACACAAGUGCCAUCUCUGUGGCAGGGCAUUCAGAACAGUCACCCUCCUGAGGAAUCACCUUAACACACACACAGGUACUCGUCCUCACAAGUGCCCAGACUGCGACAUGGCCUUUGUGACCAGUGGAGAAUUGGUUCGGCAUCGUCGUUACAAACACACCCACGAGAAGCCAUUCAAGUGUUCCAUGUGCGAUUACGCCAGUGUAGAAGUCAGCAAAUUAAAACGUCACAUUCGCUCUCAUACUGGAGAGCGUCCGUUUCAGUGCAGUUUGUGCAGUUAUGCCAGCAGGGACACAUACAAGCUGAAAAGGCACAUGAGAACCCAUUCAGGGGAAAAGCCUUAUGAAUGUUAUAUUUGUCAUGCUCGGUUUACCCAAAGUGGUACCAUGAAGAUGCACAUUUUACAGAAGCACACAGAAAAUGUGGCCAAAUUUCACUGUCCCCACUGUGACACAGUCAUAGCCCGAAAAAGUGAUUUGGGUGUCCACUUGCGAAAGCAGCAUUCCUAUAUUGAGCAAGGCAAGAAAUGCCGUUACUGUGAUGCUGUGUUUCAUGAGCGCUAUGCCCUCAUCCAGCAUCAGAAGUCACACAAGAAUGAGAAGCGCUUUAAGUGUGACCAGUGUGAUUACGCUUGUAGACAGGAGAGGCACAUGAUCAUGCACAAGCGCACCCACACCGGGGAGAAGCCUUACGCCUGCAGCCACUGCGAUAAGACCUUCCGCCAGAAGCAGCUUCUCGACAUGCACUUCAAGCGCUAUCACGACCCCAACUUCGUCCCUGCGGCUUUUGUCUGUUCUAAGUGUGGGAAAACAUUUACACGUCGGAAUACCAUGGCAAGACAUGCUGAUAAUUGUGCUGGCCCAGAUGGCGUAGAGGGGGAAAAUGGAGGAGAAACGAAGAAGAGUAAACGUGGAAGAAAAAGAAAGAUGCGCUCUAAGAAAGAAGAUUCCUCUGACAGUGAAAAUGCUGAACCAGAUCUGGACGACAAUGAGGAUGAGGAGGAGCCUGCCGUAGAAAUUGAACCUGAGCCAGAGCCUCAGCCUGUGACCCCAGCCCCACCACCCGCCAAGAAGCGGAGAGGACGACCCCCUGGCAGAACCAACCAGCCCAAACAGAACCAGCCUAUCAUUCAGGUUGAAGACCAGAAUACAGGUGCAAUUGAGAACAUUAUAGUUGAAGUAAAAAAAGAGCCAGAUGCUGAGCCCGCAGAGGGAGAGGAAGAGGAGGCCCAGCCAGCUGCCACAGAUGCCCCCAACGGAGACCUCACGCCCGAGAUGAUCCUCAGCAUGAUGGACCGGUGAUGGCGGAGCCUUGUGCGUCGCCAGGACUUCUCUGGGCUGUGUUUAAACGGCCCGCAUCUUAAUUUUUCUCCCUUCUUUCUUUUUUUGGCUUUGGGAAAAGCAUCAUUUUACCAAACAUACCGAGAACGAAAACUUCAAGGAUGAUGUUAGAAAAAAAUGUGAUUUAACUAGAACUUGCUGUCUGAUGUUAGCAAAUCAUGGAAUGUUCUGAGUCCCUGAGGGUUUACUGUGAAGUGCUGAGGACAGUGUUGACAACUAACUCGUUUUCCUAGAUGGAAACGGAGACAUUGACCCCUCCCUCCAUGUGGUAAACCACUCCAGAAUGGCCACCAGGCUUCCCAGAGUUCUAUGGUCUUCUUCCCAAGAGAGUUUUUAAUUGUAAAUGCAUACUUGGGAAGGACUUAGAGUUUUAAACUGUUUUUUGCUUUUGCUUUUCCCUGACUCCCUUUGCUUGGAGUCAGCUGCACACCAGUAGUAUGGCAUGCUACGAUCAGGUUCUGUCCUGAAAGCUUUGCCUCUUUCUUGGCAAAGUUUCUGGUAUGGUCAAGCUUGUAAAUAACUUUUUUUACAUUUUAAUCUUUUCCAUUAAUUAAGAGGUUGAAAAGAAGUGCAGUGUAAGAAAACCCAGCAUUUUAAUUACUUGCAAAUUAAGUUACCACAGACUCUGUAGUGUGUAAAUGUUGACAAGGAAUUGGAUCACAAUCAUGUAGCAGAAUGGCACCCAGACCACUGCCCACCAGUGACGGACAUGCACGUGGCAGAUCAUGAUUUCCAGCCCACGGAGCCAGCAUUUGAACCUUGUAUAAUUAACUUUCAGUUAUGAUUUCCCAUCGACAUUUUCUUUGCCCUGUUUGUAGCUGAUUGUUGUGUUUUAUAAAUCUUCUGUUAAGGCAGAAGGGUGAUUAUGAGUGGUUCACAGCAGCCCUUAUAAGCUGGGCCAGAAAAUUUCACUAGGUCAGUAAUUUAAACCUUGGAUCUUCAAAAAAUAAAAUAAUGUGAAGCAAAACCAACUAAAAAGUGAUUCUUGCACAUGAACUGUCACAUGUUUAAAAAUGUGUUUUUUAGAGAGCCUCAGUCUUACUGAUUUCAAACACUUUUUUCUUCUGUGUAUUGCUUUUAAGAGAGCCAUCAGUUAGCUAUCAGACUCUAGGUUGAUGCAUUUUGUACUUAGCUGUACUGUGUGAUAUUUUUCAUUAUUUUAGGACGCCAACAUGAGACCUGUAAUAAAAUAUGUAAUGGGGUUGAAAGCUGGGGAGGAGGAUCUACUGCUGUACAGCUAAUAAAUCAUAACGGAUUAACAAGUGCUCCAAAGA